CCUGACCUCGCACCCAGCUCGGAGCCCGGAGCGUGCCUCGGCGGCCUGUCGGAGCUGUUUGUGACGGUUUCCAGGCAGCCCAGGGCCAGGCCGCGGCUCCUAUCUGCAGCUGCAGGGAGAGAGAGGAGGAACCCCGUGCGAUUCUAGAGACGAUUUCACAACAAGGAGAAAUCAGCUUUGUGCUUACAUGCCGAGCAGCCAGCACGGUUCUUCUUUGCCUGUCCUCGGGGGAAAUCAGGGCUCUGAGAGUGGAGAUCGAGAUGGGCUAGUGGGUGGCGGAUGGGACGCUGCACGGCCAGACCCUGGACUGUGUUUUCACCAUGGAGCAGCUGAGCUCAGCAAACACCCGCUUCGCCUUGGACCUGUUCCUGGCGUUGAGUGAGAACAAUCCGGCUGGAAACAUCUUCAUCUCUCCCUUCAGCAUUUCAUCUGCUAUGGCCAUGGUUUUUCUGGGGACCAGAGGUAACACGGCAGCACAGCUGUCCAAGGUCAGCAGAAACAAAAAAAAGGGUCUGCUUUCCUCCCAUCUCCCUACGAAUGGACAGUCUGCAUGGAAAGACUUUCCAUUUCAACACGGUUGAAGAGGUUCAUUCAAGAUUCCAGAGUCUGAAUGCUGAUAUCAACAAACGUGGAGCGUCUUAUAUUCUGAAACUUGCUAAUAGAUUAUAUGGAGAGAAAACUUACAAUUUCCUUCCUGAGUUCUUGGUUUCGACUCAGAAAACAUAUGGUGCUGACCUGGCCAGUGUGGAUUUUCAGCAUGCCUCUGAAGAUGCAAGGAAGACCAUAAACCAGUGGGUCAAAGGACAGACAGAAGGAAAAAUUCCGGAACUGUUGGCUUCGGGCAUGGUUGAUAACAUGACCAAACUUGUGCUAGUAAAUGCCAUCUAUUUCAAGGGAAACUGGAAGGAUAAAUUCAUGAAAGAAGCCACGACGAAUGCACCAUUCAGAUUGAAUAAGAAAGACAGAAAAACUGUGAAAAUGAUGUAUCAGAAGAAAAAAUUUGCAUAUGGCUACAUCGAGGACCUUAAGUGCCGUGUGCUGGAACUGCCUUACCAAGGCGAGGAGCUCAGCAUGGUCAUCCUGCUGCCGGAUGACAUUGAGGACGAGUCCACGGGCCUGAAGAAGAUUGAGGAACAGUUGACUUUGGAAAAGUUGCAUGAGUGGACUAAACCUGAGAAUCUCGAUUUCAUUGAAGUUAAUGUCAGCUUGCCCAGGUUCAAACUGGAAGAGAGUUACACUCUCAACUCCGACCUCGCCCGCCUAGGUGUGCAGGAUCUCUUUAACAGUAGCAAGGCUGAUCUGUCUGGCAUGUCAGGAGCCAGAGAUAUUUUUAUAUCAAAAAUUGUCCACAAGUCAUUUGUGGAAGUGAAUGAAGAGGGAACAGAGGCGGCAGCUGCCACAGCAGGCAUCGCAACUUUCUGCAUGUUGAUGCCCGAAGAAAAUUUCACUGCCGACCAUCCAUUCCUUUUCUUUAUUCGGCAUAAUUCCUCAGGUAGCAUCCUAUUCUUGGGGAGAUUUUCUUCCCCUUAGAAGAAAGAGACUGUAGCAAUACAAAAAUCAAGCUUAGUGCUUUAUUACCUGAGUUUUUAAUAGAGCCAAUAUGUCUUAUAUCUUUACCAAUAAAACCACUGUUCAGAAACAAGUCUUUCAUUUUCUUUGUAAGUUUGGCUCUGUUGGCUGUUUACACCCAUGAAUUUUGGCAUGGGUAUCUAUUUUUCUUUUUUACAUUGAAAAAAAUCCAGUGGUUGCUUUUGAAUGCAUCAAGUAAAGAAGAAGAAAAGAAUACAUCCGAUGCGUAGAUUCUUGACCAUGUAGUAAUCUAUAAAAUUGCUAUAUCCUCCUGAUAGCCAUGGGAAAACAUGAUAAGAUGGUCAUUUAUUUUGCAGUUAGAAUUUUGGAAGCCACAAAAUAGACAGACACCCUGACUGUUGAAGGGAGGUUUAAAAACAGAUAUUCAAUUGAAAUGUAAGAGAGCACCCCAAUUGAGAGCCCAGGUUACGAAGACAAGCUUGCCUCGCCUGACUUUUCUGUCCCUUGUUCUGCAGGAUUAGUAUUCUGUUACAGACCUCUAGUUUUUAGACUCUUCAAUUAAAGGGCCAAUGGUUAUAACCUGCAUUCCCUUUUUUGUUCUUCUUUAUGUAUAAUAUAUAGUUCAUGUGGCGCUGCAUGAAAUCAAGAAGUGGGUGUCUUAGGAUAAAAGAUACCAAGAGUCUACAAAAAUAACCAUGUAGUAAGAUAAACUGCUGAACAAAGGUUUUACUGUUAGCCACCUUCUCAUGUGUUUUCUUUUCUCUUUUUCUUUUUCUUUCUUUCUUUCUUUUUUUUUUUUUUGAGACAGAGUCUUGCUCUGUUACCCAGGCUGGAGUGCAGUGGCACGAUCUCAGCUCACCGCAACCUCUGCCUCCUGGGUUCAAGUGAUUCUCUUGCUUCAGCCUCCUGAGUAGCUGGGAUUAUAGGCAUGCACCACUAGGCCUGGCUAAUUUUUGUAUUUUUAGUAGAGAUGGGGUUUUUCCAUGUUGGCCAGGCUGGUCCCGAACUCCUGACCUCAGGUGAUCCGCGCACCUCAGCCUCCCAAAGUGCUGGGAUUACAGGCAUGAGCUACCAUGCCUGGCCUUCUCAUGUGUUUUCUGAUUAAGGCUCUUGACUUCCAAGGCUGUGUGGGGAGAUGGGGUGGGGGCUCUUGGACUGAUAUAAAACUUUGUCAAAUGUAGUUCUUUGAAUGGAGCUUGAAACGCCGCAUAUUCUUGCUCCCACAAGGAUAGUGGGCAUCAUGAAUUAAUAAAACGUCCUAGGAUUCUGCAAGCUA